GGGGCCCACCACGGGCCCACCAUGUGGGCUGGCACCAACUCAGGCUCUGUGUUCGCCUAUGCACUGGAGGUGCCGGCAGCAGCAGUGGGUGGUGAGAAGCGGCCUGAGCAAGCGGUGGAGGCCGUGCUGGGCAAGGAGGUGCAGCUGAUGCACCGGGCGCCUGUGGUGGCCAUUGCCGUGUUGGACGGGCGUGGCCGCCCACUGCCCGAGCCCUACGAGGCCUCACGGGACCUGGCGCAGGCACCUGACAUGCAGGGUGGUCACGCUGUGCUCAUCGCAUCUGAGGAGCAGUUCAAGGUGUUCACACUGCCCAAGGUGAGCGCGAAGACCAAGUUCAAGCUGACGGCCCAUGAGGGCUGUCGUGUGCGCAAGGUGGCACUGGCCACGUUUGCCAGUGUGGCCUGCGAGGACUAUGCUGAGACCUGCCUGGCCUGCCUCACCAACCUGGGUGACGUCCACGUCUUCUCGGUGCCUGGCCUGCGGCCCCAGGUGCACUAUUCCUGCAUCCGGAAGGAGGACAUCAGCGGCAUCGCUUCGUGCGUCUUUACGCGCCAUGGCCAGGGCUUUUACCUGAUAUCCCCAUCAGAAUUUGAACGCUUCUCCCUAAGUGCCCGGAACAUCACAGAGCCGCUCUGCUCUCUGGACAUUAACUGGCCCCGCGAUGCCACCCAGGCCAGUUACAGGAUCCGAGAGUCACCCAAGCUGAGCCAGGCUAACGGGACCCCAAGCAUCCUGCUGGCCCCACAGAGCCUUGAUGGAAGCCCUGAUCCAGCCCACAGCAUGGGACCUGACACCCCGGAGCCACCCGAGGCUGCACUCUCACCCAUGUCCAUCGACUCAGCCACCAGUGCUGACACCACGCUGGACACGACAGGGGACGUCACAGUGGAAGAUGUGAAGGAUUUCCUGGGCUCCUCUGAGGAGUCAGAGAAGAACCUGAGGAACCUGGCAGAAGACGAGGCCCACGCCUGUGCCAUCCUGAUCAAAUGAGGAAGGCCAGAACUAUCCCGACCUCCACCUGCCCUGCUCGGAGCUGGAGUGCUGGAUCCCUGGCACCUGCCUGGCCCCUUAACAUAGAACCACGCCUGCUAACCUGUAGGCUCCACUGGGACCUGCUGUCCUGUCCCGCCUGACCCUGGGCCCUGGAGCAGCACCAGCCCCAGGGUGUGGGCCUGGGACCUGGGCCAGAACUGAGCCCUCCUGCAGGCAUUUGGCUGCCCUGGGGGCCCACUGCCUAGGGAAGAGGACAGGUGGGGCCCAGCACCUGUGCCACCUCCCCCCCUCCACACACCAUCCUUCCCCCUCACUUUGCAGAGUAUUUUUCCUUUUUUUUUUUUUUCUUAAAGACGGAGUCUUGCUCUGUCGCCCAGGCUGGAGUGCAGUGGCCCCAUCUCUGCUCACUGCAAGCCCCGCCUUCUGGGUUCCCGCCAUUCUUCUGCCUCAGCCUCCCAAGUAGCUGGGACUACAGGCGCCCACCACCACGCCCAGCUAAUUUUUUCUGUAUUUUUAGUAGAGAUGGGGUUUCACCAUGUUAGCCAGGAUGGUCUCGAUCUCCUGACCUCGUGAUCCACCCACCUCAGCCUCCCAAAGUGCUGGGAUUACAGGCGUGAGCCACCAUGCCCAGCCCUGCAAAGAGUAUUUUUCUAGCGCCUGGGCUGGACAGUUGUUUCUAAAACUAAACUAUUUUGGUACCUGCUUCUGGGCCAGUCCCCAGCCUGUCAUGAGUGUGUGUGUGCGGGCAUGGAUGUGACUGGGAGCUCUGCUGGGCACCCACAUCUGGGGCCUAGUCAGGUGUGUGUGUCCGGCGGGGGGGGGGGGCAGGGGGGGGGGUCAAGAUGAGUUUCCCUGUAGAUUGUACCUUGGGGUUUUUUUCUGUCGUUUUGUUAAAAUUAGCGCCAUUUUAAUAUUAAAAAUACUGAUUUUUAAUAUUGAAAAUAAAAGCAUUUAAUAUCUCUUAAA